AGUUUAAGGAGGCCUUCCCCCUGGCUUCACGUUGUGGAGUCGAAAGGAACCUUGAAGCGGAGAAUGAGCUCGUGACGUGGACCCGAGGAAAAAACCUGCCAACCAGGAUUUAAUAGAAUUCAGCUCUUUCAGGCUUUGGAGGGAAGGCGAUUUGAACGGGAUUUCAAUGAAAAACCCUGUCCCUUCGGCUUUUUUUUUUUCCUCUCUCGGGUCUCGUCACGUGAUGGUCCUACUUUAUUUUUAAAAAUUAAAUGGCGCAUAUUCCCCAGCAUCCUAAAUCUAGUGCAACCUAGUGGCAAGUGGAGAAAAAAAUAACUGCCAACCUGGCUUCCUACGAGGUCCCCCGGAGUUCUCGCAAAGUUGCGACCCAGUUGGCAAAAAUACAGUGUGUGCAAAGACUCAACUGGACAUUGCCACCAAGAAUCAAGAGAUUUUUGGGGACUUUAGCAAGAAAACGUUAUUUUUAAAAGCCCUGCUCCAAAGCUGGUUACAAAUGAAUACUGCGUUUCCAGUGACAGGUUGGGCGAGCAGAAAGGAAAUCUUACGACGGAGUCUUGCCCUGUCGCCUAGGCUAGAGUGCAGUGGUGUGAUCUCGGCUCACUGCAACCGCCACCUCCCGGUUUCCCGUGAUUCUCCUGCCUCAGCCUCCUGAGUAGCUGGGAUUACAGACACCAUGCCACAAGGAGAGUGAUCUCUUCCCCUGUUUUCACAAUGGAGGACUCCGGAAAGACUUUCAGCUCCGAGGAGGAAGAAGCUAACUAUUGGAAAGAUCUGGCGAUGACCUACAAACAGAGGGCAGAAAAUACGCAAGAGGAACUCCGAGAAUUCCAGGAGGGAAGCCGAGAAUAUGAAGCUGAAUUGGAGACGCAGCUGCAACAAAUUGAAACCAGGAACAGAGACCUCCUGUCCGAAAAUAACCGCCUUCGCAUGGAGCUGGAAACCAUCAAGGAGAAGUUUGAAGUGCAGCACUCUGAAGGCUACCGGCAGAUCUCAGCCUUGGAGGAUGACCUCGCGCAGACCAAAGCCAUUAAAGACCAAUUGCAGAAAUACAUCAGAGAGCUGGAGCAAGCAAAUGACGACCUGGAAAGAGCCAAGCGCGCCACGAUCAUGUCUCUCGAAGACUUUGAGCAGCGCUUGAAUCAGGCCAUCGAAAGAAAUGCCUUCCUGGAAAGUGAACUUGAUGAAAAAGAGAAUCUCCUGGAAUCUGUUCAGAGACUGAAGGAUGAAGCCAGAGAUUUGCGGCAGGAACUGGCCGUGCAGCAGAAGCAGGAGAAACCCAGGACCCCCAUGCCCAGCUCAGUGGAAGCUGAGAGGACAGACACAGCUGUGCAGGCCACGGGCUCCGUGCCGUCCACGCCCAUUGCUCACCGAGGACCCAGCUCAAGUUUAAACACACCUGGGAGCUUCAGACGUGGCCUGGACGACUCCACCGGGGGGACCCCCCUCACACCUGCGGCCCGGAUAUCAGCCCUCAACAUUGUGGGAGACCUACUGCGGAAAGUCGGGGCACUGGAGUCCAAACUCGCUUCCUGCCGGAACCUCGUGUACGAUCAGUCCCCAAACCGAACAGGUGGCCCAGCCUCUGGGCGGAGCAGCAAGAACAGAGAUGGCGGGGAGAGACGGCCAAGCAGCACCAGCGUGCCUUUGGGUGAUAAGGGGUUGGACACGAGUUGCCGCUGGUUGUCCAAAUCAACAACCAGGUCGUCCAGCUCCUGCUGAAGCCUGUUCUUGGUCUUUUCCAGUUUAUCAUAAGCGGCCGCCUUCUCCUCGUACUGCUGGGUGAGGUUCUCGAUCUCCUUCUGGAACCUCUUCUUCCCCUCUUCCAGAGCUUCCACGGUGCUGGCAAAGUCCUGCAGCUUCUUCUUCGAGUCGGAGAGCUACAAGGACAGCGUCCAGGGUAGGGUGAGAGGGGGACCAUGAGUGGCCCCUGUCCCUGGCCCCACAGACUCUGAGAAGCGAAGACCAUGUCUCCUCGUUGGAGAAACCCAAUAGCAGGGGAAGCUGGGGGGUCAAGCACCAUCGCACCAACACUCCACCGCGAUCUGCCUGCGGGGGAUCUCAGCGCAGAGAAGUUGAGAGGACCCAUGAAGGAAGCAAGGACACGGGGCAGGCACCUGGAUGUUGAGAGUGGAGAUGUGGCGCUCCAGGUUCUGCUUGGCCUCCAUCUCCUCGUCCAGCUGGUCUUGCAGGCUGUUCCGCUCCUCCUCCAGCUGGCGCAGCUUCGUAGACACGUUGAGCUUCUGCCGGGUUUCUUCUUGAAGCAGCUCCUGCAAAAGGGAUGCAAAGAGGUCCCAGGGACCUGCCCCGAGGAAGGCCACCCCCCAGGUCCCCUGGAUGAUGUGGCAGGACACUCACCUGGGUGUCCUGGAGCUGGGAACUGAGGGACGCCACGUCCUUGGCCAGCUUAAUGGCCUUCCCCUCGGCCUCGUUAAGCAUCCCUGUGACGCUCUCAACUUCAUUCUAAGGGUGCCAAGAGACUGGUUAGUCAAAGCCUCUAGAAGGGGAUCCUCGUUGAAAGGAGCCCUUUUUACUCAAAACACAUGGGCUAGUACUUGAGGUGUUCACUGAUUGAGAAAAUACCCGUGAGGUAUGGGACUCUGAUAAAAAAAAAAAAAAACACACACACACACAAAAAAAACAGAAUCUGUGGCUUGAAGGGAACUCCGUCACCUAUGAGUUGGGACCCUGGCCCUAGACUCUGUGGUUCUAAGAACUUAUUUGAGCCCCAAUGGUAUUGACUGGGACCUGAUCCCACUAAAUGGAUCCUAGAUCCCUGCCAAGGUUGGUAGAGACAAAGCAGCAGGUCUGAGAGUCCAGACGAGGUGCUCUGGCUGGUCCACUCUCUAAGGCUGGAGAAGGGAGACCAGGAUGGUACUUGAACGUCCCAGGGAUGCUGUCCCAUCCCUUCCUUCCUCACUCCUACUCUUUGACCCUGAUGGCCAAAGCCAGAGACGCAGGCCCUAAAGGUAAAAACGUCCUCUCUGUAUUCUCUGGCUUUUACUCCCUAGUGUCUCUGCAUAAGUCCCUUUGAGGCUGUUAGCCUACCCCUCCAUCUCUUCCAUUGACAAGGAGGAUAUGAAUGAUCUUGACACUGCUUAUAUGAGGGCGGCAAAAGCCCUGCUCUCAACUGCAUGUGAGAAAAAAACAUCUCACUUAAUUCUUCCCUCGCCCCUUGGUCCCUGGCUGUGGACAUGUUAAACAUUUGUGAAAACUUUGGCCACGUCCCCAUGAGUGGCAAGGCAGGGUAAAUGGCUAUGCCAAGUGAAAGAAGACCAAAGACAAAAAGACCAUGUCAUUCAGCAGCUUAAAACCCCUCAACAGCUUCACAUUGCCCAGAGUAAGGAUCAACAUACAUGUAAUAGGUUCUCAAAAGCCCUACAUCAUCUGGGUACAAGCUCCCCCUCCAACCCCACUCUGUACUAUCUCCCCCUACCCCCAACCCCAGCUGGGCACUCCAGCUCUACUGGCUGUAUGUCUCUCUCCUAAUUUUUCUACUUACCACAGGGCCUUUGCACACGCUGUUCCCUCUGCCUGGUAGACUUAUCCAUGCUCCUUAGGGAAGCCUUUCGUGGCUCCUCCUCCCCCAGGUUAGGCCCCCUGGUUAUUUACACUUGGGCAUCAUGUGCCUUCCCUUUGCUGCAUCAUUUGACAUUCAUUUGUGUGAUUAUUCAUGUCUUUCCCUUCCCUUCCCUUCCCCUUACUCGGCUGGAGUCCUACUGGGGCAGCGACAGUGUCUCUUCUUCCUUGCUGUUGGAUCUCAGGAUUAAGCACAGUGCCUGGCAUACAGCAGGUGCUCAAUAAAUACUUAUCAAAUUGGAAAA